GUUUAUUUGCAGCUGGGCCAACUCCGCGGCGCAGGCGGCGGCGGAGCGCGGGGAGCUCGCGGCGGGUCCAGCUGCCGCAGCACCAUGCCCGAGCCCCCCUCCGGGCAGACGCCGCGCGCCGCCGGGGCCCCGGUAGGGGAGGAUGCCAGACGCCCGGGAGAGGCCAGGGCAGCAGCGGCGGCGGCGGCGCGAUGGUGGUGACCACCUCUGCCCGAGGCGGCGGCGGGGACCGCACACCCUCCCGGCGGCGGGGCUGCGGGCUAGCGCCGGCCGGGGCCGCGGCGCUGCUGGCCGGGGCAAGCUGCCUGUGCUACGGCCGCUCCCUGCAGGGCGAGUUCGUGCACGACGACGUGUGGGCGAUCGUGAACAACCCCGACGUGCGGCCCGGCGCCCCGCUCCGCUGGGGCAUCUUCACCAACGACUUCUGGGGCAAGGGCAUGGCCGAGAACACCAGCCACAAGUCCUACCGGCCGCUCUGCGUCCUCACCUUCAAGCUAAACAUAUUUUUGACUGGUAUGAACCCAUUCUACUUUCAUGCAGUAAAUAUAAUUUUACACUGCUUAGUGACUCUUGUGCUGAUGUACACCUGUGAUAAAACUGUCUUCAAGAAUCGUGGACUUGCUUUUGUAACGGCAUUGCUUUUUGCUGUACAUCCUAUUCAUACUGAGGCGGUGGCUGGGAUCGUUGGCAGAGCGGACGUGUUAGCGUGUCUGCUGUUUCUAUUGGCCUUUCUCUCGUACAACAGGAGUCUGGAUCAGGGCUGUGUUGGGGGAAGUUUCCCUUCCACGGUGUCUCCCUUCUUCUUGCUGCUCAGUUUGUUUCUGGGGACCUGUGCGAUGCUGGUGAAAGAGACAGGCAUCACGGUGUUUGGAGUGUGCUUGGUUUAUGACCUCUUUUCCCUUUCCAACAAGCAAGACAAGUCGAGCAAUGGGGCCCUCUGUCCACGCAGCCCACAGCAGCCCGGGAGCCCCCAGCCCUCCUCACUGCCAGGCCAUCCUCACCGGGAGAAUGGGAAGCAGCAGCGGUUCCCUCACAAAGGAGCUUGGGGUGGCUGCCACUCUCCACUGCCACCAGAACCCAAGAGCAGUGGAUUCCCAGUGUCCCCACGAGCUGUGUGGUCCAUGAUGAGGUAUCUGAGAGCAAGCAGCAAUAGAAAUUUCCUGCUUACCAUGAGACCAUUUUUAAAAAGGGCCAUUUUGGUCCUAAGUUAUGUGCUUGUCAUUUUGUACUUCCGUCUGUGGAUAAUGGGAGGAUCUAUGCCCCUCUUUUCAGAGCAGGAUAAUCCAGCUUCAUUUUCGCCUUACAUUCUUACGAGAUUCCUCACCUAUUCCUACCUCUUGGCCUUCAAUGUGUGGCUUCUGCUUGCACCCGUGACCCUGUGCUAUGACUGGCAGGUCGGCAGUAUUCCUCUGGUAGAGACCAUAUGGGACAUGCGGAACUUAGCCACCAUCUUUCUGGCGGUUGUGAUGGCCUUAUUGAGCCUGCACUGCUUAGCAGCCUUUAAGAGACUGGAGCACAAGGAGGUUUUAGUCGGCUUGUUGUUCCUGGUGUUCCCGUUCAUUCCAGCCAGCAACCUCUUCUUCAGGGUGGGUUUUGUGGUGGCGGAGAGAGUCCUUUACAUGCCUAGCAUGGGCUACUGCAUCCUUUUUGUGCAUGGACUGAGCAAGCUCUGCACUUGGCUGAAUCGAUGUGGGGCCACCACCCUGAUUGUGUCCACUGUGUUGCUGCUGUUGCUUUUCUCUUGGAAAACUGUGAAACAGAAUGAAAUUUGGCUGUCAAGAGAGUCCCUAUUCAGGUCUGGAGUUCAAACUCUGCCCCACAAUGCCAAGGUUCACUACAACUAUGCCAAUUUCCUGAAGGACCAAGGUCGGAACAAGGAAGCGAUCUACCACUACAGAACAGCUCUCAAGUUGUAUCCACGCCAUGCAAGUGCGCUCAACAACCUUGGAACACUGACGAGAGACACAGCAGAGGCAAAGAUGUACUAUCAGAGGGCUCUCCAGCUCCAUCCACAGCAUAACCGGGCUCUUUUCAAUCUGGGGAAUCUCCUCAAGUCCCAGGAGAAAAAGGAAGAAGCUAUCACCUUACUGAAGGAUUCCAUCAAAUAUGGUCCAGAGUUUGCAGAUGCAUAUUCAAGCUUAGCUUCGUUAUUGGCUGAGCAGGAGCGGUUUAAAGAAGCUGAAGAAAUAUACCAAACUGGAAUAAAGAACUGUCCAGACAGCUCAGAUUUACACAACAACUAUGGGGUUUUCUUAGUUGAUACUGGCUUACCAGAAAAGGCAGUGGCCCAUUACCAGCAGGCCAUCAAACUUAGCCCCAGUCAUCACGUGGCCAUGGUGAACUUGGGAAGACUCUACAGGUCACUGGGAGAGAACAGCAUGGCUGAAGAAUGGUACAAGCGCGCCCUGCAGGUGGCACACAAAGCUGAGAUAUUGUCACCUUUGGGAGCACUGUAUUACAACACUGGCCGAUACGAAGAGGCUUUGCAGAUUUACCAGGAAGCUGCAGCACUUCAGCCUUCUCAGAGGGAGCUCCGCUUGGCACUGGCUCAGGUUUUGGCCGUGAUGGGUCAGACAAAAGAAGCUGAAAAGAUGACCAAUCACAUUGUGUCAGAGGAGACCGGAUGCCUUGAAUGCUAUCGCCUCUUGUCAGCCAUCUAUAGCAAGCAGGAGAACCACGACAAGGCACUUGAUGCUAUAGACAAGGCUCUCCAGCUGAAACCAAAGGACCCAAAAGUCAUUUCUGAACUUUUUUUCACAAAAGGAAACCAAUUAAGAGAGCAGAACCUUCUCGACAAAGCUUUUGAGAGCUAUAGAGUGGCUGUGCAACUAAACCCAGACCAAGCACAGGCCUGGAUGAACAUGGGUGGCAUCCAACACAUCAAGGGAAAAUAUGUGUCUGCAAGAGCUUAUUAUGAGAGAGCCUUACAGCUGGUUCCAGACAGCAAACUGCUGAAGGAAAAUCUUGCCAAAUUGGAUCGCCUAGAAAAACGAUUACAAGAAGUUCGAGAAAAGGAUCAAACAUAGCACCACCGUCUGACCCAACCUCAUAGGAUAAUGUGGUGCCUCUGAAAGGGGAGUGAUGGAAGCCUUGCUUUCACAUCAGCAGGGGCACAACUAAUGAGAUUUUCUCUCAUUCCGAGUUCAGGGUGACACAUUUUGGGACAUCUGCUGGUAGCCCAGUGCUGAAGGACUUGCUUUUCCAUGAAGAAGACGAAAACAGCAAACAAGGGCAAGAAGGUCUGAGAGGGAAGGAGAAUGACAUUUACACAUUUUACAGAUUUUUGUUUGGUUUAACUCCAGAUUUCUCUUGAUAUAUCUCUGUGCUUUUGAGACCUGGAGAUCUAAUUCUGUUUAGACAUUUUUUGUCCCAGAAAUACAGAAGCUUGAAAUGCUAUGAAGGCAGAGCUUCUAUUCUUUAUGGGAUGAAAUAUUUCAAAAGAGGAUAAAUCCUCUGUGGUAAGCCAUUUGGAAAAUCCUACCAAGAAUUGGCUUAUUUAAUUUUCCAGAACCAGGAAUGAGUAUCUAAUAGCUUUUGUAGAACCUUCCAGAAUAUGUGGGGAAAAAGGGCUAUUGCUAAGUGAGCUUUAUCUAAUAUCCUCCUAAGAGUUUUACUAGUGCUUUUUUGAGGAAUUACAGGGAAGCUCCUGGAAUUGUACAUGGAUAUCUUUAUCCCUAGGGGGAAAUCAAGGAGCUGGGCACCCCUAAUUCUUUAUGGAAGUGUUUAAAACUAUUUUAAUUUUAUUACAAGUAUUACUAGAGUGGUGGUUCUACUCUAAGAUUUCAAAAGUGCAUUUAAAAUCAUACAUGUUCCCGCCUGCAAAUAUAUUGUUAUUUUGGUGGAGAAAAAAAUAGUAUAUUCUACAUAAAAAAUUAAAGAUAUUAACUAAGAGAAAUGUCCUACUUUAUUAUCUUAAUGUUCAGACAUCAUGAGAUUUAUUAUUUUUUUGAAAAAUAUAUUGAACCAUUGAGGAACCUUUAUGAUGUAUCACAGAAAUCUUCAUAGAUUCUAACUAGAUGGAAAAAGAGCUCUAUUUAUUUGUGUUCCUAGGCUUAAUGAGAAUUCUGGGCUUAGAACAUCAACGAUUAAUACCCAGAAUUCUUUGUUUUGAGAAUAUUAUGGAGAAUGCUCUAAAAAUCUAGGGUAAAGAUCUAAAUUCAAAUUUUAAAUAUAUAUUUAUAUUUAAGAAAUAGGAAAGGCAAAGUUGAACUCACAAUUUGACAUUUAUUUUUAGUGUUAUUUAUUUCAUAACUUAUAAAAUAUUUAAUAUAUACAUACACACUCUUCUUUUUUCUCUGUACAAAGUGGUUUUAAUAUCAGCUUUCAAAACUGAUCUUAUAAAAUGUAAAUCUAAAUUGUAAAAUAGUUAAGUUUUAACAGUCCCUCCCAAACUUUGUGUUGAUUAUUCACUUGCUAAAGAGAUGUGAGGAAUCAGCCUUCAGUUUUUUGGCAGUAGUAUAUUUUGGAAGUGAAGAAAUUGGAACACCUGUUUCUAAUUUGGUCUUCAUCAUUAGAGACAAAACCAAAACACUCCAGGCAGUACUGUUUAUAGUGCUGAGCCAGGUAGCACACAGACAUAGUAGCCUAAAGGCUCACAUAAUUCGCAUGCUCAGGCCAGGGCAGGGUAAAAAUAGCCUUCUGCUUCUUUCAACCCAGUAUCAGGAAGCACUACCCCAGUGUUAUUAUUUGUUUUGUCAAGGUAAGUCUAAAUAAACAAGAAAAACUUCUUCGGAAGGCAUGGCGAAGGGAGUAUUUUAAAUGAAAAUGAUUACAGAAUUUGAAUUAGCAUGCAUCUCUUUGUGUGCAACAGUAAUCCAAGAAUGUAUAUGUUACCACUACAACCAUUUGUUUCUAAUAGUUUUUUCAUGUUAUAUAACAUAAAUGUAUCCACAACCUUAAUUAAGAACUAUUCUUCCCCCAAAAUCAUAGUCCUAGUGUCAAGAAACAUACUCCAGUGUUUAUUGUAAAAUAACAACCACACCCUCAAAUUGAAAAAAGUGAAUGUCUAGGACUUUAUUACAACUUUUCAGAAUAAUCUGUAAUGAAAACUCAUGCUUAAAAAUUUAAUGGAAAAGACUGAGCCCCAAAUUUUGAAUAGUGAUUACGCCUUACUUGAAGUGCUAAUAAAGGUAGGAGAGUACAUUUGUUGGAAUAACAGAAAUGGUGAUUUCAGCCUAAAAGUUUCUGAGGGUAAAGGAUCACAUGACCUUCAGGAAACUCUCUGCCUCCUGUAGGUGCUUUCCUAUCUCCCCCAUCCUUCCCUACCCCUUUUCCCUUUUCCUUCCUCUCUUUUUCUCUCACUGUCACUCUGUCUACACACACUGGCAUCUUUUGAACACUAAAAGUAAGCACUGUUUUUUAAAAAAGUAAUUAUUUGUUGGAUCAGAUACUUUUAUCCCAAGUGAAUACCUUCACUGAGAUGUGGCCAAUGCAAUAGUUUCACAGUAAAAACAGUGCCUAUAAGAAAAUAGAUCACAUACUAUUUUUCAAUGAUAUUAAGUGUAUUUUGUAACUAUUUUCAUUUGGUCCUUGUAACAUGAAAUAAUACAUGGAACUUACCUUUAUAAUAAAAAUGGAGUGCCCUGGUUCAUCAUAGAGGUGCAUCUAGUUUGCCCUUAAUGGAAGUAUACUUGCUGUGUGGAUUGAUAGCACCUUCUUGAAAUGGAGGAGCUCAGCUGGCCUCAUGGAUGUGCAAUUUUUGCAGUCCCACAGGGCCUUGCAUACAGAAGCACCCCGAGCUCAGUUGAAUGUCUGUUUGAUUUUUUCUUAUUUAUUUUUUUGAGACACAGUUCCACUUUGUCUUUUUGUCACCCAGGAUGGAGUUCAGUGGCACAAACAUGGCUCACUGUAGCCUCGACCUCCCUGGCUGAAGGGAUCCUCCCACCUCAGCCUCCCAAGUAACCGAGACUACAGGCAUAUGCCAGCAUGUCCAGCUAAUUUUUGUAUUUUUUGUAGAGACAGGGUUUCACCAUGUUGCCCAGGCUGGUCUCAAACUCCUGGGCUCAAGCGAUCUGCCCACCUCUGCCUCCCAAAGUGCUGGGAUUAAAGGCAUAAGCCACCAUGUCCAACUGAAAUUCUUAAUAAUUAAUAAUUUUUGAGCAAGAGGUCCACACUUUCAUUUUGCACUGGGUUCCCAAACAGGUCCUGGGUAGGAAGGAUGGCUGAGGAUAAAACAGGAGUUGCUUUGGCCUGGCUGAACAUUUGAACCAAUGAUCAGAGUUUCAUUUUAUGAUUGUGUUACUCUGAACAGAUUUGCUAUUUUUUUCCAGCUACAUUUAGAGUUCCUCAUGUAUAUAUCACCCCUCUUUUUCCAGUCCAUCUAACCUCUCCUUUUUUUUGUGCCUAGAAUCAGUUCUCCUUGCCUUCAAAAUCCCUGAUAAGUGUCCAUUUCUUUUUGUAUCCUUUGAUGUAGAAGCCACAAGAAUGGCUUUAGCAGCUUAUUUUAAUCUUAUGAAUUAUUCAUUCAGGAUUUUUUAAAUGAUUCAGAUGCUUUCAAUCUGUUAACAGUAUUUAUAAAACAUGUUUCAGUGAUACAACAUAGGUGAACUAAACCAAAGAUGCAAAUGCCUUGGAGGAAAAGAAAUUGUAUUAUAGAGAAUCCUGAGAUAUAUCCUUUUGGGUUGUUUAAUUUAAAGCCUAUCACAAAACAAAGAGAAUUGUCGCACUUUAAUUCCAACCUCCUGCAGUACUUCACAACCCUUAGCAUAAGAUUCUGAAAUUUGUAAUAGGUGGUACCUAGUUUGAUGCAGGGUUUUGCAGCAGUUGUGCGAAUGCCUCUGCGCAACGGCCUUUCAGUCAGACUAAAUGAGAAAAUCCAAACUGUCCUAUCAAAACUGACCCACAAUAACUGUACUCUGAGGCGAAACAGAGCAAAUGUGGGUUUCCUGUUUUCAUUGUAAAACAUUCCAGGUUCUCAGAUUGAAGAGCUACAUUCAGCUGAUAGUUGACAUCUGUUCCCUCACACGUAGUGGCUCUCAACACGGGCUGCACUUUGGAAUCACCUGAGGACCUUUCGGAAUCUUCGGUUGAAUCAUCCUGGCUGUCCUGGUGAUGCUUCUUAUGUGCAGCUAGGCUGGAGAACCACUACAGGGCUGACACCUGGAAUGGGAGCUUGUAACUUUUACAAAAUAAUAGAUGUUUAUCAUCUUUUGCAAUUUUUACUUUUAAGUCUAUACUAAAAUGAGCCAAAGAAGUCUUAACAAUGAUGUAUGGCACAAUUGGUUGGUUGAGGCUAUCAUUCCAUGAUUACAAAUAGGUGGUUAUGUGGGGUGGUUUUGCACUUGUGGCAAUUGGACUGCAAUUUGGCCUUAAAAUGACACAAUUCCUCGUUCUCAGAUGGAGAGGAAUUGCCUUGAAAUUUGCAUGUACCAGACUAAGUGCCAGUAUAUAUAUGACUGAUAUUUUCGUGACUCAUAGAAGGUGUCCAUGGUAUAGAGUUUAUGCCUACAUCUCUAUCUUUAUUUUGGGCACACAUGAGCUUUUGUUAAUUAUUUCUUUGUACUUGUUAGAAUCUGUUUUUGAAAAAAAAAAAAACUUUUGCUUUGAUUUGUGGUGGAUUCACCUUCUUAAAAUAAUAAAUUUAGAGGAUAUUAGGAAUGACAUUCAAAACAAAUAUAGUGAGAGGUGAUUUUUUAAAAAUUUUUGUUCCUGGUUUCCAAAUUAUGUUUACUUUGAUUUGAUUAUAUGUUGGUAUCUCCCAAAUAUAGGUUAACUUAGCUAUUUAAAUGGUAUCUUUUGACAUUUAAAAAGAAUUAAGUACCUGUCAAAUCUAGCAUUGAGGUUGCAGUUGAAUAAGAUAAAAGCUUAGGAUGUCAAAAAAUAAUAUAGAGAAAUAUUAUAAGAUUUUAUGAUUAUUCUUGACGUUUUUGAUGCAAAAGGAAAAUAUGCUGAAUAGUUCUUCCAAAAAAUAUUAUUUCCCUCAAUAUUUUAUUUGUAGCCAUGUAAUUUAAAGAGAACAGAAAAUAACUGCAAUCAAAAGUAUGGUUUAAUAUCAAUCAAAGUGGCACAACAGAAUUGAUAAGAUCUUUAUAACAAUCAAUUGGCUGAUAUUAAAAUAUUGAUUUUAAUUGAUCUUUUCAAUUAAAAUCUUUAGGGCCUGUAACUCAUAAAAUCAGCAUCCACCACAAUAUAUGGUCAUUAUUGGUUUGUAAGCAUAGAUCACCAUUGACUCCUACCUGGAGAGACAUGUCUAUUUCUAAAAAUCCAGUAGUUUCUUUGCAUUCUCAGUAGUACACGUUGUAUAUAUAUAUAUGUAACAAAUUUGGUAGUUUUCAGUAUGUGUGAUGUCCUUUGGGGGUUAUUUAUCUUGCUGGUCCAUAGGAGGGGUACACUACCCCAAGAAUCAAGACAUCUGAGUUCUAGUUCUAGUUCUAGCUCUGCCACUGAAGAGCCACCUUACCUGGGGCAAGUUAGCCAUUGUCUCCCAGUCAUGUUUACCACCCAUGAAAGGACUCGUCGGUUUGAUGUUUCCAUUAAGCUCAAUGAGUAACUCUAAUAGUUACUCUUGAAUCUGGAUUGAAAAACACCAUGCAUCUGAUGAGAUAAUUCAUAAAUGUUGCCCCUUUUUUAAAUGAUACAACCCUAAAAGUGACUGAAUUGCCCAAGUGCUUGAACAUGGCAGAGGUAGUUACUCCUAUUUUGCAGUUUGUGCACUUAAAAAUUCCUACAGUGAUUGUUACUUUACUGGGGAAAAAAGAUGAGGUGAAACUUCCUCCCAAGGAAUUAAAAUAUCUGUAGAAGCCAUGGCUUGCUUUUAUAAUGUGGAAAUCAUUUGAUUUGCUGUAAUUCACGCAGAUCCCUCCUUUUGUCAGGGGGAAAUGAUUUGCAUCAUGUUCUUUUUUCAUAAUGCUUUUACUUCCUGUUUGGAUCAGUUGUAUGUAAAUGUACAUUUUUGUUACUUUGGCUGUGCCCGUUAGAAUUUAUCUUCCAUAAAGUAUUUCUCCCAUUGAGUCUAAUGAUGUAUACUUUGCCUAGGUCUUUCCAAAAUUAAAUUUAUGUAAAUGUCUAUUUUAUAUAAAAUAUGAUUAAAAUAA